GAGAUGCAGGUGGAUUCUUGGGCAUUUGCUAUUAACUUCCUUCCAAAAUGUCACCAUUCCUGUAUCUGGUUCUCUUGGUACUUGGGCUUCAUGCUACAAUCCACUGUGCAUCACCUGAAGGCAAAGUAACAGCCUGCCAUUCAUCCCAACCAAAUGCCACUCUCUACAAGAUGUCAUCCAUUAAUGCUGACUUUGCAUUCAAUCUGUACCGGAGGUUCACUGUGGAGACCCCAGAUAAGAACAUCUUCUUUUCCCCUGUGAGCAUUUCUGCAGCUUUGGUUAUGCUUUCCUUUGGGGCCUGCUGCAGCACCCAAACUGAGAUUGUGGAGACCUUGGGGUUCAACCUCACAGACACUCCAAUGGUAGAGAUCCAGCAUGGCUUCCAGCAUCUGAUCUGUUCACUGAAUUUUCCAAAGAAGGAACUGGAAUUGCAGAUAGGAAAUGCCCUCUUCAUUGGCAAGCAUCUGAAACCACUGGCAAAGUUCUUGAAUGAUGUCAAGACCCUCUAUGAGACUGAAGUCUUUUCUACCGACUUCUCCAACAUUUCUGCAGCCAAGCAGGAGAUUAACAGUCAUGUGGAGAUGCAAACCAAAGGGAAAGUUGUGGGUCUAAUUCAAGACCUCAAGCCAAACACCAUCAUGGUCUUAGUGAACUAUAUUCACUUUAAAGCCCAGUGGGCAAAUCCUUUUGAUCCAUCCAAGACAGAAGACAGUUCCAGCUUCUUAAUAGACAAGACCACCACUGUUCAAGUGCCCAUGAUGCACCAGAUGGAACAAUACUAUCACCUAGUGGAUAUGGAAUUGAACUGCACAGUUCUGCAAAUGGACUACAGCAAGAAUGCUCUGGCACUCUUUGUUCUUCCCAAGGAGGGACAGAUGGAGUCAGUGGAAGCUGCCAUGUCAUCUAAAACACUGAAGAAGUGGAACCGCUUACUACAGAAGGGAUGGGUUGACUUGUUUGUUCCAAAGUUUUCCAUUUCUGCCACAUAUGACCUUGGAGCCACACUUUUGAAGAUGGGCAUUCAGCAUGCCUAUUCUGAAAAUGCUGAUUUUUCUGGACUCACAGAGGACAAUGGUCUGAAACUUUCCAAUGCUGCCCAUAAGGCUGUGCUGCACAUUGGUGAAAAGGGAACUGAAGCUGCAGCUGUCCCUGAAGUUGAACUUUCGGAUCAGCCUGAAAACACUUUCCUACACCCUAUUAUCCAAAUUGAUAGAUCUUUCAUGUUGUUGAUUUUGGAGAGAAGCACAAGGAGUAUUCUCUUUCUAGGGAAAGUUGUGAACCCAACGGAAGCGUAGUUGGGAAAAAGGCCAUUGGCUAAUUGCACGUGUGUAUUGCAAUGGGAAAUAAAUAAAUAAUAUAGCCUGGUGUGAUUGAUGUGAGCUUGGACUUGCAUUCCCUUAUGAUGGGAUGAAGAUUGAACCCUGGCUGAACUUUGUUGGCUGUGGAAGAGGCCAAUCCUAUGGCAGAGCAUUCAGAAUGUCAAUGAGUAAUUCAUUAUUAUCCAAAGCAUAGGAAGGCUCUAUGUUUGUAUAUUUCUCUUUGUCAGAAUACCCCUCAACUCAUUUGCUCUAAUAAAUUUGACUGGGUUGAAAAAUUUUCCCUUUUCUGUCUUCUGGGGAAUAGCUAAAAAGCAGGUCAGGUCUUCGUAUCCCAGUACUCCAAUAAGAUCAAUGGACAUAAAACAAUGCAGAUGCAUUGUCUUAUAUGUGAACUUCUCAACCCCCUUCCCACUGUCCCAUUAGUAGGAUUCUCUGAGUUCUUGCCAGAUCUGACACUGGUAGGUUGAAUAAAGGAACUCCCACUAUGGGGAUGAGUUACAGACUGAGACAACUGAACAAGUUACUGAACAAGCAUGGGACAAUACAGCAAGAGAUAAACUUGCCUGUCCAACCCCACCUUCCCCCCAAGAAAACAUACUUCCACCUUGCCAAUGUAUAAGCUGGGAGUGGAGAAAGAAAGUAAUUCAUUCAUGUCAUAUCUCAUAGACCCUCUUUUUCUGUAUCCCAAUCAGACUCCUUUCCAUAUAUAGCACCCCUGUCCCACUUGUUUAAGUAGGAAUCUCCUUUUUGGCUCUAAUUUCACUGAAUAUUGGUACUUUUGUAUCCCCAGAUCCUUCAACAACCUUCCCUCUACCUGUACAUGCCAACUCAUUACCACCUACCAAACUAGAUUUUAUUUCAGACACUAUGUAUUUAAAGCUUGAGUAUAAAUGGCACAGUGAGUGGUAAUGAUGUAGUAUCUGAAAUUCUAGCCCUGAGGUAAAACACUUCAGUGACAGGAAAAUAGUAAAAAAAAUGCAUAAGUACUGUUGCAGAUGUUGUACUUCCAUAUUGAAAUAAAUAUUUAUGUUUAGAAAAGCA